GGAUUAAACUCUCCAAUUGAAAGGUAGAGCAUGGUAGAAUGGAUAAGAAUAGAUAAUCCAACUAUUCUGUCUAUGAGAGUCUCACCUGAGAUACAAAGACAUAAGUAGCUUAAAAGUGGAAGGAUGAAAAACCAUAUUCCAUGCAAAUAGUAAGUAAAAGAGAGCUGGAGUGACUAUACCAAUAUCACACAAAAUAGGCUUUAAAUCAAAGCCUGUUACAGAAGACAAAAGACUUGAUACACUGAUAAAAGUGUCAUUCCACCAAGAAGAUAUAUAAACUAUAAAUAUAACACACCUAACAAUAUAACCUCAAAACAGACAUAUAAACUAACAGAAUUGAAGGGAAUAAUAGACUGUUCUACAACAGGACUUUGAGAAUUUAAUGCCCCCACUUCCAAUAAUGGAUAAAAGAACUAAGCAGAAGAUCAAUAAAUAAAUAGACUUGAAUAACAUGAACCAACAAGACCUAACCAGUUUAUACAGAAUACUCCACUUAACAACAGCAGAAAACACAUUCUUCUCAUGUGCACAUGGACCAUUCUUCAGGAUAGAUCAUAUAUUAUGCCACAAAAUAAAUCUCAAUGAAACGAAAAAGAUCAAAAUUAUACAUGGUAUUUUUUUCUGACCCAAUAGAAUGAAACUGGAAAUCAAUAACAAAUGGAAAACUGGAAAUUUCAUAUAUAUGUGGAAAUUAAACAAAUCAUGUUUUACAAACCAAUGAGUCAAAGCAGUAAUCACAGGGGAAAUUAGAAAACACCUUGAGGAGCAGAACUUCUUCCACAAAAGACCUGAAAGAAGAUUGGAGUGUAACUACACCAGUGAAAGAGGUCAAACCAGGAGAAAAGAGAGAUGAAAAGUGUCCAGAGUUAAAGCAGGAAAUGGAAACAUUGCUCUCAGAGGCCAUUCGUCUCAUUAAAAGUCUAGAAACUGACCGGGCAGACGCUGAAGAAGCUUUAAAACAACAGAGAUCAAGAAAGAAUAUGAUUAACAUGAAAAUUGACUCUUGGUCAGUCUGGAAACUUCAAGAACUCCCAUUGGCUGUGCAGAAAGAACAUGAGGCCUAUUUGAGUGAUGUUAUAGAAUUACAAUGGCAUCUUGAAGAUAAAGCUAAUCAACUACAACAUUUUGAAAAACAAAAGACAGAGUUAGAAGAAGCAAAUGCAAAGAUUCAAGCAGACAUAGACUACAUGAAUGAACAUGGCCCUCUACUGGACUCUAAGCAGAAUCAGGAACUUCAAGAUCUGAAGAACCAUUAUAAAAAAAAAAUGGAGGUAAUGGACCUACACAGAAAAGUUAAUGAAGAACUUGAAGAAGCUUUAGAAGCCUGUGAAAAUGCCAGAUUGAAGGCUCAGCAAAUUAAAGAAGAGAUUGAUAAGGAUAUUUACCAGGAUGAAAAAACCAUAGAGGCCUACAAGAGAGAGAUAUAUCAACUUAACAGUCUAUUUGAUCAUUACUCUUCAUCAGUGAUAAAUGUUAAUACUAAUAUUGAGGAGAAGGAAGAGGAAGUGACUGAAGCAAUAAGGGAAACAAAGUCAUCAAAAAAUGAAUUACAUUCUCUAUCAAAAAUGCUGGAAGAUUUGAGAAGAGUUUAUGACCAACUAACCUGGAAGCAAAAAAGUCAUGAAAAUCAGUAUCUGGAAGCAGUUAAUGAUUUUUAUGCUGCAAAAAAAACAUGGGAUAUUGAGCUUUCUGAUGUUGCAAAAGAUUUUUCAGCUAUUUCUUUGGCAUGUACAAAACUGACGGAAGACAAUAAAAAACUUGAGAUUGAUAUUAACAAAAUAACAGUAAAAACCAAUGAAAGCAUACGGAAAAAAUCAAAAUACGAAUCUGAAAUAAAAUAUUUGACAAUAAUGAAGUUAAAGAAUGAUAAACAUCUCAAGAACAUCUAUAAGGAGGCUUAUCGCAUUGGUACUCUUUUCCACCUAACCAAACACAAGACAGAUGAAAUGGAAGAUAAAAUAGCAGAAGUGAGAAGAAAGUUCAAGGGUAGAGAAGAAUUCCUGAAAAAACUCACUCAAGGUGAAGUGGCUGCUGGAAUGGUGCUUCAGAAAAAACUAUAUUCCAUUUACGAAGUCCAGGCACUUGAGCGGAAAGAGCUUAUAAAAAAUAGAGCAAUAUGUGCCAUGUCACUGGCAGAACUACAGGAACCUCUGCUUCAACUAGAAGAUGAAGCUGAAAGAAUCAGAAGUCUCGACAAAGAACAUUCUGUUAUGCUUAAUAAUAUAAUUGAUCAGAAAGAUCUUAUUAGAAGAAAGGUGGGAAAAGUAAAGAAAAAAUUACGAAAAAAGGGGAAGAAAACCCUUGAUGCAUUAAUAGAAACUGAGAGUAAACGCUCAGCAAUUUUUAAAGACCUAGAAGCAACUAAAAGUAAGACAAUGAUUUUUUAUGCAAAAAUAAAUGAAUUGAAUGAGGAAUUAAAAGCAAAAGAAGAAGAAAAGAAAAGUUUUGAUCAGACACUUGAAAUAUUAAAGAACAAAUUUAUAACUAUGAGAUUUAAAAGGGAACAUGCACAAACUGUGUUUGAUCAUUAUAUGCAAGAGAAAAAAGACUGUGAAGAGAGAAUCUUUGAGGAAGAUCAGAGAUUUAGAGUGCUCCUUGCUGUAAGACAAAAAACUCUUCAAGAUACCCAAAAAAUAAUAGCUGAUUCACUUGAAGAAAAUCUGCGUUUAGCUCAAGAGUAUCAACAGCUACAGAUUACAUUCUUAAAAGAAAAGGACAAUUAUUUCAAUAUAUAUGAUAAACAGCUAUCACUUGAUACUUCAAUUAGAGAUAAGAAACAGGUUGCAGGCUUCUUACCUAAGAAACUUCCAAACUCUCUGCCAAUUAUAUCAGAUGAACUCUCAAAUUUUCAGCUCUGUCAGCUGCAGAGAAGGAUGCACACACUGUGGCAGGAGCACUUCAAACUGGUGGUCCUCUUCAGCCAGAUGAGGCUGGCCAACUUCCAGACAGACUCUCAGGAGAGUAUUCAGAAAAUAUUAGCUGUGCAGGAGGAAUCUUCAAAUUUAAUGCAACACAUCUUAGGUUUCUUCCAGACUUUGACAGAUGGCACAUGCGAAAACGAUGGUUAAGCAAACAACCAAUGUAUCUUGGAUGCUGAAAUAAAAGACAAGAAAAGUCACACAGUUCAGAUAACAGUGUAAUUGGACAUUCACCUGUUUGCCAUUUCACACUUCCAUGAACGAAAAACUCACUCACCUCCCAGCAUGCUUUGCCACUCUUUUACUCACAGCAAAUCCAUAACAAUGAAACAGGUGACUUUCAUGCUGCUGUCAGGAACGAUCUAAUUUCAGCUCUGGGUGACUGAUUGCAAUUGGCUUUGCCUCAUCUGAUAAUUAAUCUAUGUCACCAUUAAUUGGAAGAGAGAAUAAUUACUGGCGGUGUUGACAGUGACUGUUCGCUUCCCCAGAUUUCCCUAUCGUCUUGGCCCAAAUAAAGGCUUUGCCAUUCAGUACUUAAAGUUUGUGUAAACUGUAACAAUAUCUAUGCCCAUGUGACACUUUGAGACACUCUGUCUAAUGUACUUUUGUUUUUGUGUUUACCAGUCUUUUUUAGCUCACUGAGAGCUGUCUCUCUCAAUCACUCCUCAAUGUUCUAUCUUAAUUUUGUGGAAGUUUAAAGUUUUCAAUGAGCUGGAGAUGAAUGAUUAAUGAAUAAAUUUAAAUGCUUCAUUUUG